AGAGAGGGAAGCCCCGGCGGUGAGAGUCGGCCCAAAAAGCGGCGGCCGUUGGAGGUGGCUGCGGCAGCUGCUACCCGUUCCUUCCUGUGCGUGACUCAGCCUCAUCUCUGCCCGGGUGCGUGCCUGGCCGCCGGGUCCUCUCGAGAGUGUGCAUCCGCGACUGGAGAUGGGGAGUUCUAGGGUUCUUUUGUCACUACUGUUGGAAUUACAGGCUUUGAGGCAGGAAAGGAUUCUGCACAGGCAUUCGACUGCAAGUUGUUUGAUGACUUCGUUCCAUGUUCAAGUUUGUGCUGUUCUGCCUGAGAUGUGGCCUCAUGGAUGAGCUGGUACACGACUUAGCCUCAGCCUUGGAGCAGACAUCUGAGCAGAAUAAGCUUGGUGAACUGUGGGAGGAGAUGGCGCUGAGCCCCCGACAGCAGAGGCGGCAGCUUCGGAAACGCCGAGGUCGGAAGCGUCGUUCUGACUUCACUCACCUGGCAGAGCAUACCUGCUGCUACAGCGAGGCCUCUGAGUCAAGUCUGGAUGAGGCCACUAAGGACUGUCGAGAAGUGGCUCCGGUGACCAAUUUUAGUGACUCUGAUGACACAAUGGUAGCCAAACGACACCCAGCUCUCAAUGCCAUUGUCAAGAGUAAGCAACAUUCUUGGCAUGAAUCUGACUCCUUUACUGAAAAUGCACCUUGUCGACCACUCAGGCGCAGGCGGAAGGUGAAGCGAGUGACAUCAGAGGUGGCUGCUAGCCUUCAGCAGAAGCUGAAGGUGUCAGAUUGGAGCUAUGAGAGAGGCUGCAGGUUCAAGUCUGCUAAGAAGCAGCGUCUGUCCCGCUGGAAGGAGAAUACUCCCUGGACCUCAUCAGGCCACGGAUUGUGUGAAUCAGCAGAAAAUAGGACUUUCCUAAGCAAAACAGGAAGGAAAGAAAGGAUGGAGUGUGAAACAGAUGAACAAAAACAGGGCUCUGAUGAGAACAUGUCAGAAUGUGAAACCAGCAGUGUGUGUAGCAGCAGUGACACUGGGCUCUUUACCAAUGAUGAAGGGCGACAAGGUGAUGACGAACAGAGUGAUUGGUUCUAUGAAGGAGAAUGUGUCCCAGGAUUCACUGUCCCUAAUCUUCUGCCCAAGUGGGCUCCUGAUCAUUGUUCUGAAGUAGAAAGAAUGGAUUCUGGAUUGGAUAAAUUUUCAGAUUCCACAUUCCUUUUACCUUCUCGGCCAGCUCAAAGAGGGUACCAUACUCGCUUGAAUCGUCUACCUGGAGCUGCAGCUCGAUGCCUCAGAAAGGGGCGAAGAAGGCUGGUUGGGAAGGAGACCAGCAUAAACACUUUGGGGACUGAGAGGAUAAGCCAUAUCAUUAGUGACCCUCGGCAGAAAGAAAAGAAUAAAGCGUUGGCUUCUGAUUUUCCUCACAUUUCUGCUUGUGCACAUGAGUUCAAUCCCCUGUCUCCCCUUUACUCCCUGGAUGUUCUUGCCGAUGCUUCUCACCGAAGGUGUUCACCAGCACACUGCUCUGCCAGACAGGCAAAUGUACACUGGGGACCACCAUGUUCACGUGACAUCAAGAGGAAGCGGAAACCAGUGGCCACAGCAUCUUUGUCUAGCCCCAGUGCAGUUCACAUGGAUGCAGUGGAGCCAACCACACCAGCAUCACAAGCCCCCAAAUCACCCAGCUCUGAGUGGUUGGUGAGGACCUCUGCAGCAGAGAAAGCCACAGACGCAACUACUGCUACAUUUUUUAAAAUGCCACAAGAAAAGAGCCCUGGAUACAGCUAGAGAGCAGGACUUCACCCUCCAGGAGCUGACUGGGUGUUGCUGAAGCAAAUGUUGGACUUUGUGUUAGAUAGUCUUGCAUAUCUUAAUCGACAUUCCCAGUCCUUUCACCACCAGAACCAACUCCUCUUUCAAACACAGCAGUGGAUUCUUUCUCUCAGAAGAUCAUGUUGUGGGAAUCUUUUUUUUAAAUAGUGAAAUAUUGAGGCAGCAAUUUUUUACAAAAAGGUCAUCCUCUGCUCUAUUUGUUACCUUGUUAUUGCUGUCUCAACAUUUACUACAGCUCCAUUUACAGAACUGUUGCUUUUUUGCAGUUGUCUUUGUUCUUGAAAAACCAGUAACUGCUUCUGCAUACCUUUUGUGUAGAGCUUUUAAUAUCAUUUGAGGAAGUUCCAAAUUUGUAGCCAGUUCCAAACAAAUUUAAAUAUUGAGUUGAGACCUGUAUGGAAUUGUGUUCGCAGGAGAUAAGGCUUGCCUUUGAGCCUACUCUUGAUUCAUGCAGAGUGCCAAUAAGAUAAAUCAACCAAGUUUUGGGGCCUCAAAAGAGACACCAGCAACUGGGCCUUGAGAACUUCCAUUUUUUUGCAGAUUGUCUGCAGAAACUCAGACAGCUCAUCAGCAGCAGCAGCUGUAUUGUAUUUUACCUCAUCUUCAGAGUUUAUGUUCUACUGAAAGAGGACGUGUGUAUACACACACACACACACACACACACACAGAUUGGUAUAAUGGAGAAGAUGGUUUAGGUGUACAGCAAAUUUAAAAUAGUCAGUGGAUUGUGUCUUACUACUUCAUGUCCCAGUGUAAGCCUUUAUGUCCUAAGCAGGACUUUAUUGUUAGUAUUAUAGGCUAAUAACCUGCAGCAGAAAUUCAUACUCUAUUAUAAUAAUGGCUUCUUGGGGCCAUGCUUUGGGGAAGUAAAAUGUCUUUUUGACAUGCCUUUAUACUUGGCGUGUUUAUGAUGGCUCAGCUGCAUGUGGAGUUAUAUAUACAGUCGUGCCUGAAGUUGGAUGCUACUUUGUCAAAAUGAGAAAUAAGUGAUGGCCUGGAGCUGCUGGAGAGAAGCCACGCUUUCUAGAAAAUAUUAUCAGGAGUGUCUGUCAUUCAUUCAGGGGCCUAGCUGACAGAAGGGCUCUUUUUUUUAUACCAAUGAGUGCGUUUACUCUGAAAUACAUAGAAGCUCUUGGUGAAGUGCUCCCUGCUCUGGUCACAUUGUAGAGGGACUCCCACUCAUGCAUCUGCUUAUUUUCUGUCUUAAAUAGGUGCUGAAUGGGGCAGCACCUCCUUCCCCCAAAGUGCGAUUGCCCCUGUUUCCCAUACGAAGUGUAAUGACGGGUUGCUUUUAAAAUUAUAGUCCUUAUCAAUGGAAACUCCAGAUUUCUUUAUCAAAGGGAGGUGGGUGGGCAUGAAUCUAGUUGGAAAAGGGGACUUGAAGCUAAGUUUACAUGGCACUUUAAGACUGAGAACAUAUCAAUUGUUCAUAAUCAGGAAUAUGGUAGAGGGAGAGCAGGUGUAGAUGAUGGGACGGGAAAGUGCUGAAACCAGCCCAGCAGACCUGUGAGUCGCCUCUGGUUCUCACGCAGCAGUGUGUGUGUGCUCACAGGGAUGUUCCACCCCUGGUUCUCAUGCAGUAGUGUGGGAGAGUGCUGAAGCCGGCCCAGCAUGCCUCUUAGUUGCCUCUGGUUCUCAUGCAGCAGUGUGUGUGCUUACAGGAGUGGAGAUGAUGGGAUGGGAGAGUGCUGAAGCUGGCCCAGCAUGCCUCUGAGUCACCCCUGGCUCUCAUGCAGCAGUGUGUGUGCUUACAGGGACUUCCCAGGCUGCACUUCCCUUCCCUGUGGGCUGCACCCGUAGAAGUAUAGAAAAUGUAAUGUCUGUUGAAUAUAAAAUCGUACCACUGAAUUGUUCUAGUGAUGAGGUUAGAUUUUGUUGUCAUGUGCAUUGUCACCAUAGUGACCCGUGGCAUAUAUUUUUAACAUACUUGGUUGGGUUUGAGAGAAAUCUGUGGACGUAAUUUUUUGUUUGUGUCAAGCUCUAUGACUCAUGCAGUGAUUGGUCCCAUGAUCAUGGCCUAUUAGUGAAAACCUCCAAAGGUCAGGUGGCCAAGGUGUUCCCACAUUUUUUCUAUAUAACUUGUUUCCUAAUAGUCUGCCUUUCUACCUAUGAUUAAAAAUAAUUUUUAUAUACAACAUUAUUUACAUUUCAAACAUCUCUACGAAGUCAUGCCAUUUUAAGGAGAUGAAAACAGCCACAGAGUUGAGUGACUUGCUCCAAAUCACAUAACUAAGCCAGGACUAGAAUCCCAGACUUUCAGAUUUUCUCUGCCCUGGGUUAUAAUCUCUUGUUUUUCAGUGAUAGACCUGAGUCAGUCUGAGAUGCUUAUUUAUGAAACAGUAUACCAUGAAUAUUUAUUAUCUUUCUUGGGCAUGCUUUUCUACACAUUUUGAAUACUUUCAACAGGGAUUACCCAAGAAUGCAACAUCUACCUGUAAUAAAUGGGGAGAAAAUUAGUUGCCUGAGAGAACAGAAUAUUAAGCACACAAAUACUUUCCAACACAGGGUUGUAAAUUGUGCUCCUCAUUUUAAGGUGCUGUACGUGCAUGUUUAAGGAAUUAUUAAUCAGUGUAUUCUGCUUGCUUUCUGUAUUAACCAGUUCCAGAGGAUAGCCUUAGAAAUGAGUGUAUUUUGAAUCUUAAAGUUUCUUUAUAUGCGGCACAGUGUAUAAUGUCGUAAGUUAAGAAAAAUCUGUUAUCUUUCAAAGAAGUUACGUAGUUUCAAAAAUGAGGUUUUGUAAUCAGUGUUGAAAAAACUCUGAACUAUGACUUACUUUGAGGAUGAUCCUUGAGCUCAUGUAUUUGAUCUGCUCAAAAGUAAUAACUAAAGCUGAGUUAAACAGUUGUUAUUUAUUUCAGGGUUCUGAUUUUUCCCAGCUGGCUACACAAAUGGCCUGUCUGAAUCCUAGUUUAGUGUGUUUUCCACGAUGGGCAGAAGUCAGAACAUUAUCUGCUUCUGUGAGGAUCAUAAUAAAAAGUUAGUUUUAAUUACGAGUUUAAAGGAAUUUUAGAUUUUUUUCAGAUGCAGUAUUUUAAAGGAACAAAACUCCUGUGUUGCCUUUUGUUGUUGUUGUUGUUGUUGUUGUUUCCUAGAGACAGGUUCUUGAUCUGUCACUCAGGUUAGAGUGCAGUGAUGUGUUCAUAGCUCACUGUAACCUUGAACUCAUAAGCUCAAGCCAUCCUCCUGCCUCAGCCUCCUGAGUUGUGAGGACUAUGGAAGUGUGCCACCAUGCCUGGCUAAUUUUUUAAGUUUUUGGAGAGAUGGGGUCUUGCUCUGUUGCCUAUGCUGGUCUUGAACUCCUAACCUCAAGCAAUCUUCCUGCCUCAGCCUCCCCAGGUGUUGUAAUAAUAGGUGCGAGCCACCAUGCCCAGCCUUGUGUUGCCUCUUGGUAAGAAAUAAUAAAAAGAAAUUAGUAGCUUGUUUACCUGGUACCAGAUUUGGAGGGGGCUGAGUAUAAUUUUUACUGAGUGGUAUGUGGUUGGAAAAUAGGCCACAUUUAGCCUUGAAUUGUUUAGAAAUCAAAUGCGAUUCAGAAUUGAAGAGGACAUUGCUGGGCUAUGAAAUAGGGUACUAACAAGGCUAUUUUUGUAGCAAAAUGGCCAAAAGCUGAAAUAAAUCUUCUUAGUCUGUGAUGCUUGUAGCAUCCUUUGUUAAGUAAAGCACAACACCCUGGACAAGCGACUAGUUAUGACUUCCAAAUAGAUUGAUAAUAGCCUUGCAUGUUGUAGUUAGAGACACUGUAGCUGUAUCUGUAUACCUGUAAUAUAGCCUGGGAAGUUCUGUUGCUGCAGAGUUAUCAUUAAAGUCACUUGGAAUUGAAAAAGAUACAGAGUGUUGAGACAAAGGAACUAGGCUGGCACAGUCAUUGCUGAUGCGAUGGGUUCUCCACUUUGGCUCCAGGCGAAGGCUCCUGGUGGUGAUGCAUGAUUGAUUUCAGGUCUUUGUUUCAUUUUGGCUUCAUUACUGUGAUUCUGAGCCACACAGGUUUUUCCCCCUGGGGAGAAGACUAUGUAAAAAUCUCAGCGUUAGAAGCUGUGUUCAGUGCCCUAUAUGUCUUGUGAACCUAUCUGAGCUGGGCUGAGAGCAGAGUGGCUUACUGUAGCAGCUGUGGAUGCAGUCUAGUUGGAGGCAUGGCUUGGAGGACGUCAUGGUUCAUGCGAUGGUUGGAGGGAUGGUAAAAGCAGUUAGCUCUUGUCAGCUGCUUCCCUCUGCUAGUGCUUGAGCUGCCAAUUUUAUUUGUCAGUAUUUCCUGAUCUCCCACUCCUGUUGUGAAAGGUCACAGAGUUACUGUCACUGGCAACAAUUUCGCCCCUUAGAAGAAAACUGGUACAGAGGGAAAGGGUGAGGAAAAUGGUGAGUUCCAUCACUCAGAACUAAAUGCAAGUGGUAGAGAGAUGCUUUCUCCUGUGUUAACGUCUCCAAAAGAUGAACAUCAAAUGCCCGGAAACAGCAACAUCAAAAAGAAGGAAGAUGAGAAGUAUUGUUGAAGAGUAUGGACCUACAGGGUUUUUAACAAGUCCAGCAAAACAAACUAUGGCCAAAAGAAGAAAUUUUUCUGUCACUGCGAGUAGACAUCAUAAAUGCUUGGUAAAAUUGCCAGAUUUAGGGAAUAAAAAAUUUUUAAAGUACAGUGUUGAAGAAUGGGGCAUGUCAUGAAGACAUUCAGCAAAGAAGCAAUCUUGGCAAGGUGGAGAAGUGGGAAGCAAUGGGGAGAGAAAGGGAGAUGCCCAGAGCAGGAAUUCUCAAUGUGUGGUCCCUAGGCCAACAGCAUCAGCACAUCUUGCCCUCACCAGACCUACUGAAUCCGAAACUCCCAGCGCAAGGCCCAGCAGUCUUCAACAAGCCCUCCAGGGGUCUUUGGUGCAUGCUCAAGUUUGAGAACCAUAGGCUUUGCCACGGUUAAAAAGAUGUUUUAAUGGACUGGUCUCCUCCUAAGCUCUGAGGUGCUCUCAUAUUCCCUCCAUAAGUAAAGAGAUUUUUUUUGUAUAAUUCUUUGCAGAAACUGUUAAUGUCUUUAUUUCUCAUAUUUUUUUUUUCCCCUACAAGCUCCUGAAAGAUCUUUUUGAAGAAUUGACAAAGGAUGCUAUCAAGGGCUAUGUUUAGGUGGAUGGAAAUAACCUUUUGAAAAUGGAUAAAGCCUGGGUGUGGUGACUCACGCCCAUAAUCCCAACACUUUGGGAGGCCAGGGCGGGAGGAUUGCUUUAUUGCAGGAGUUGAAGACCAGCCUAUGCAACACAGUGAGACCUUGUCUCUACAAAAAAUUUUAAAAAUUAGCUGGCUGUGGUGGUGCAUGCCUGUGGUCCCAGCUACUUGGGAGGCAGAGGCAGGAGGAUCACUCAAGCCCAGGAGGUUGAGGGUGCAGUGAGCCAUGAUCUGGCCACUGCACUCCAGCCUGGGUGACAGAGCAAGACCCUGUAUCAAAAAAUAGAUAAUAAAAUAAAAAUUGAUAAAAAUAGAUCAAUGAAUUGUUAGUCUACGAAUGAUAGUCAUUUUUCACAAUUGGCAGUAAAAAUAGGAUUUGUGUAAGGUAUGAGUUUACCAUAUUUGUUCAUUAGAUCUUAGUUUCAAGGGAAAGUAUCAUGUAUUUUCCAGCAUGAUAAUGAUGAAUCAUUUAAAGUACGGCUCAUAAAAAUGAAAAAAAAAAUUGGAAGAAAAAAACACCUUGGGUACAUAGAUGUGUAAUAAAUACCUGUUGAGUUAUUGGUAAUCUCUUGCUAGGACUGAAUCUCAGUACUUCAGAGCAUGUAAAAAUCAAUUUUCUGUGAUCCCACUUAAUCACACCGUGUUUUCUUUUUUUAGAUUUCAGCUAGCAAUUUUGCAGGGGUUGGAGACCAAUAGCGAUGUCAUGCUUUUUGGUUGUUGUUAUUGUCUGACUCGUGGAUUCAGCAUUUCAGAAUAUGGUACUCUAAUCUUAAGGCUUUGAAAAGAAACCAUGGCCAUUUUUUCUUCAUAUUUUACCUUUAUUAAUUGGGCUGGGUCCUAACUGGUUGCCAGAGCCCAGAAAUCCAAGUUCUGUCUUUUCAGGGAAUAUGCAUAGCUAAAGAGUUCAUUGUGUUUGCAAAGGUGUACUAGGAGUUCUCAUUUCCUCAGAUGCUCAUGUCUGUAGGCUGUUAAGCUCUCAUUUCAAUUUUUGCAGUCUUUUAAAACACCACACUUCUUUUCCAUCUUGAAGACCAGUUAAAACUACCUCUGGCCAAAAAUGUUAGUGUUACUAGAUAUUAUCAAGGUGUGAGACUAAAAAGUUAGAAGGCUUUAAGAUGUAAAUUAUAUAAGUUAAUGUUUUCUUUCCCUAAAAGUUCUGACCCUUGCUGACCCCUCAAUCAAAUGUUUUUAAUUGAAAGGGGAAAGAAAAUAUCAGAGAACUUAAAGAUGGCCUUCGUGACUUUGACUCAAAAUCAAUGCAUUUCAUUAUGUAUGGGUCCUACACCUUGCUUCCUCAAGUGGCCAUGAAAAAAAAUCUCACGACCAUGCAAACUGAUGCCACCCCAAAGUCAUGGUAACGAUUUGAAUUGCUCUCAGUAUUGAUGUCAAACUCCCUCCUGUUGUCAGCAGCUUAUUGCAAACUGGCCAUUCUAAACCCUUUUACCCCCACCUUCUCUCAAUCUUAGCAGUUAAUCUCAGCCCUCCCCCACCACAUAACAGCCUCGGGCAGAACUUCCCACUUAGACACCCACACACACACACGCUUCCUUACCUUCUUGCCAGUGCCUGUCCUGCCCAAGACGAACCCCUUUUCCUGUGCCCUAGGACCUCUCCCUUGAUAAAUGACUUGAUCUAGCUACAGCCUCACACUCCUGGCACAUACAGCUUUGCAUUUAAACAUGUUCAGAUACUCCUUCCUUCAAACAAAAGACCUUUCCUCAACCCUUUGAAAGCCUGAGUACCACUAAGGUAUACUGCCCUUAUCUGCACUCUGUCCAUUCUGCAGUCUACCGAGGCAGUGGUUUUUAACCCUGGCUGCAUGUUAGGGUCACCUGGGAAGUUUUAAAAAGUCCUAAUUCCUGGACUGGACCACAGACCAGUUAAAUCAGCAUGGGGAGGUGGGGAUGGGUUUCAGUCUUUAAAAAGAAAUGUAGCUGAGGCUGAGAACCACCACUCUAAAACCUGGCUGCUACCCUUGCUACCAUUAAAACUGUUCUUGCUGGAUUCACCCACCAGUGACUUCUACUAUUAAAAUUUAGCCCAUAGGUUGAUUUUUAUGACACUGAUGCUAUAUAACCACUUCCUUCUUUGGAAUGCUCCCUUUCCUGACCCUACUUUCCUGAUUUUUCUGCCACUUCUUUGCUCUUUCUCAGUUUCUGUGGAGUUGUUUGGUAGGUCAGUCUAGCACAGACUGGAUGCCGGUCUCUGCCGCCACCUCCGUUAUUUCAGUGAACACCUGUAUGCCAGUGAGUUCCUUUGCCAUACCACCUUAAUGCACCAACUUAAAAGCACAGAUUAGAGUGGAGCAUUCACAUUUAUUACUGCAGGCUUCUAGGAAAGCAUAUUAAAGGUCUCUGGUCCUUCUCUCACCUCCCUUGUUCCUCCUCCAAGCCCAGUGAGGUAGGAGGAAUUGCUAAUUAGAUUAGUGAGAUUCUAAGGUGGGUCACUCCUGUUUACUUAUGAGUUGCUAUUUAUGAAAAGAUGGCCUGGACUGUGUUCCCUCUUCUGCUUUCUCCUCUUCCGGGUCUUGGACUGGUAAGGGGGCCUGUGCCCAAAAGGGGCUCCUCCACCUAAUGCUGUCUUUAAUCUGUGGCUUUCUGCUGCUGGUUAAUUUUUUAAUUUGGCUUCCUCAAGCCUUUUUGGCCUUGAACUUCAUGUUGAUUUUUAUCAAAGAACUUUUUAUUGGGGCAUCAGCACUAGCCCUAUGAAUACAGUGAAACUUGGGGUUCCACUUUCAUCAGAUGUGACCCUGUGUGUUCCUGAUGUCUUUGAAUCACUAGUUUCUGAUUCAAAAUAUGGGGUAGGUGGAUCUGAUUAGUAGUCAUAUGCCUGUGUCCUGGCUAGGAAGUCAGAAUGAGGUUAUCUGGAAAGUUGAGCUUCCUCACACAUGGGAAGGUACUUCAGAUGCUGGACAGCCAAUAAGAAUAACAAAGGUCCACCAGAACCAUUGCCCCAGUCACUGAUUGAACAAACAUUUACUGAACACUGAUGAAGCGAAGUCCUCCUCAGGGACCUCUUAGGGAAGAGGGUAACUGCCCUAAAGCAGGAUACUCCUGGGCUCCUUAGAUAUACUAUCCUUGAAACUAUUAGGCCCCUGUCCAGAGUACCUAAUAAUAAUAAUGGCAAAUAUGUAUUUGGUGGUCUGCCAUUUGGAAGCAACAUCUCACUUAUUCAACAACUCUAAAGGUAGGUACUUUUAUCUCCAUUUUAAAACAAUGAAAUACACUUACAGUUACAGACAAACUUGCUCGAGUCACAUAUCUAUUAAGUGUCAGUCAAGAUUCAGAUUCAAGUCUGAUGUUAAAGAGUGUCUGUUCCCAAUCAAUACCUCUGCUGCCUCUUUUUACAAACUGAACUGUUGGAGGGCAUGUACAUAUGCAUAAGCUGUGGGCCACUGGGCCAUGGGCCAGUGUCUGAUGAGACCUCUUUAUUGACUUGUUUGUCCUGGUGGGCUGUUUCUCUACCAGGCAACUGUGAAUGGGCUCAUCCCUUCUCUGUGCGUACAUGAUUGAAAGGAGAUAGCCGGUUUCUGUGACAUCCUCUUAUAACAACCUAGUUUUGUUCUUGAGAGUGACCAGAGCAAGAGAAAAGUCAAUGAAAUUUUGCAGAUCUUGCAAACCUGUGGCAAUAAGAAGGUAUUAUCCUUUCUGUACCAAGGCACAACUGAUUCCUAAGUGAGGGGGAUAUGUGUUCUGAGAUGUUAAUGUUAGUGAUAGACUGUUUUCAACACCUUGGUAAACAUUUCUUUUGACUGUUAGCAAAAGCUGCCUUAACAGUCUUGGCUUUUAGAAAUGCCCCUUCAUUCAUUAGAUGUGUAUGGAACACAUCUUAUGCCAAGCACUCUGCUAGGAGCUGGGUAUACAGAGAAGAAAGGCAUUCCUGCUCUCAUGAUGUUCAUGGUCUUCUGCGGAAGAGACCAGAAAAAAAGUAUUACAAUGUAGAAUGAAAUAAGAAUGACAGGGUAUUUUGGCAGCAAGGAGGAGGGCACUUUAACUCAAACUGGGCAGUGGAAGAAGUAAAAAAAAACAUUGAAAGAAAUCCUGAAGGAUAAGCAGGAGUUAAGAAGAGUGGAUGAAGCCCUCCAAGGGUAAAAGCAUGGUUUAUUCAGAGCACUGCAAGUGUUUUAGUAUGGCCCACAUGUAAAGCUUACAGAGGAACAAAGAGAGAAAGGCAAGAGCCAGGAAGUGAAGGGUCCUGUGUAUACUGGCUUACUUGUUGAGUUGGAGAACUAUUGCCGUAUUCCUCUGCUAAGCUCAGGGUGCAUUCGUGGAAACCCUACUGCAACUGGCCCAUUGUGCAUACAAAGCUGGAACUGAGAUGUGAACAGAUUUGCAUUGCCUUGAUCACCUUCCGUGGGAAAUAUAGCUAGGCCCACUUAUUGGUAGGAGCUACUGACAUGUUAAAACUAGGUUAAACUGAAUUGGAAGUAAUGGUGUAUUUGGAAUCAUGGCUGACUGAUUCCAUUACAUGUUCUAGCAUGAUACCAGUCUGAGGUUAUUCCCCUUGAACCACCGACUUAGUAGAGUUUAAUGCACAAUGUGAUGGUCUUAGUUCCUUGUACUGUUCUUCAGUGUCAAAGUUGUUCAACUACCAGUUAAGUUUUUUGGGCUUUGUUUCUCAGUAGUGACAAUAAAUUUGUGUUGAUCUAUUUACACCUUUUGGACUGAACACCUUAGCAAUCAUUGAUAUUUUAAGCCUACAGGAAGUGCCCAUGGGAUAAAACCAAUCUGCUGGCUCACACUAAGUUCUGAUCCCAUGAUUUUGGUCUCAUUAAUACCGUGCUAUAAAUAAAGUUAGCUAAAUCUUUUGAAACUGCAUAAAAGUGAAAUAAUUAUGAGUUUUGGGCCAACAUUUUUCCUGAACAGCUUCUGACUGACCAGCAUUUUAAAUUAGGCGAUGCAGUCUAGCUUUUGUACAUAGAAAUAAGAAAGUGACUUAUGUUCCAUUAUUAAAAUAGUAUAGGGAGGACAGGUAAAUUACUAAUUUUUCAUUGCUCAUAGUAGAGAAUUAAGGUAUAUUGACUAGUGAAAUAGAGGAUUAUGGGGAUCAUAUGAAAAUAUGAUUAAAGAGAUUAUCACUAGAAGAAAAAUUCAGACUGCUAAUUAUGAGAAAAAACAUGUAUGCACAACCAAACAAAUCACAAAAAUGAAAGAUGUCUAAAACCAUAGAAUAGGAACAAAUGUACCUGUCAUAUUAAUAAAAGUAAACUUAUCUGUAGAUAAAAGGCAAAAAUGUCAGCAAACACUAAUUUCAUGUUAUAAGAUUCAGAAAGGUUGAGCAAAAGUAAACCAAGCAAACACAAACAAGAAAAUGAGUUGUAGUCUGCAUAUCAGGCAAGGUUGAACUUAGGGAAAAGGAACCGGAAAAAAAAAAACCAAAAAAAACCACGACAUAAUGCUAAAGGGUGUGACUCACGAGAUAAUGUUUCUAGAUAUCUGUGUACCAAAUAAUGGAAAACCAUUUAUGUAUUGGAAACCAUAGGAGACACAGGAAGAAACAAAUACAAUGUUAGUUGGAUAUUUUAAUUCAAUUCUGUCAAUUCAUGACAGAUCAAGUGGAUAAAAAACUAGGACAUGGGAUGAUUUAAAUAAGAUACAGAAGAUCUAGUUGAUGCAUAUUAGACUUUACCCUAAAAGUGGUAACUACACUUCAAAGUAUCCAUGAAACAUUUCCCCAUUUGACUGUGUAUUAGAGCGUACAGAAAACAUAAGUUUCAGAACGGAAAAAAGGAACAACAGAUGGCAUUUGCUGAUAAAAAUGCAAUAAACUUAGAAUUUGAGGAUAGGUGGUCAGAAAAAAAAAUGCAAUAAAUUAAAGCCAGAAAACACUGCUCAUCUGCAAUCCAAAAUGUUUUUAAGCUCUUCAACUAUUCUUGGGUUGAUUAGGAAAUGCAAAGUAUUAAAAAAACAUUUCAUAUCUAAAAUAUAAACUUGUUCCUCUGAGAUACAAAUAAAACAGUGCUCAGAGGAAAAUUCAUUGCCCUAAAAUUUAUGUAUUAAAAAAUAAGAUAAAUGUCAUAUAACUCAAAAUAUUAGGAAAAGGAAUCUUUUAAAGGCAGGCUAAAAGAAUCAAGAAAAAUUAAUUAGAAAAAUGAGGAAACAAAGCUAAUUUUUAAAAUAUGUAGUAAAAUAUGUAACAUUUUAGCUAACAUUACAAGAGAAGACAAACACAAAAUAAGAAUUACCAAGUAUUGAAUAGGUAAGAGUCAUAAAAUAUUCUUUGCUCAACUGUAUGCAAACAAUUUAAAAACUUGGAUUAAAUGGAUAAUUUUCCAGGAAGGUAUAGUUUGCCAAAAAAUGACAUCAAAAGAAAUCUAAUAUAACAAUUGUCAUAGAAGAAAUGAAGUAAGUAUUUCAAUUAGCAUGACAGACUAAAUACUUUUAAAGACCCAAUGAAAACAAAGAAAUGCAUUUGGAGAAUUAACAGAAACUUUUUGUAACACCAAUUUUUUAUUUUACAUUUUAAAGCAUGGAAUGGAAUUUAUUGUAAAGACGUGUAUUUUAUAGAAUCCAAGCAAAAGCUCACCAGCCAGAGAUAAAGUGAGGCCAGCUCAGGGAAUGUGAGCAGUGGCGAUUUAUUCCCUCUGGUGUUCCAUGUUAGCCUGACACAGAGCCCCCUCUUCACAUUCUCAGGGGCUCUUGAUCCAAAACCUUUUUUAAAAAAAAUAAUUUUAGACUUAACAGAAAAUCUGCAAAAAUAGAUUUCCUGUGUGCCCUUCUCUCAGCUUCUUCUAAUGUUAACUUACAUACCAAUGGUACAAUUAUUGAAACUAGGAAAUUAACAUUGGCACAAUCCUAUUAACUACAUACUUUAUUUGAAUUGUAGCUGUUUUCCCAGUAAUGUUGUUUUUCUGGUUCGGUAUUCAAUCCAGGAUCCAUAUGUACUUGGGUCUUUCUGGGUUUUCUGUUCCACUGGUCUACUUGUGCAUGGUACCACACUGUUUUAAUUAUAGAGACUUUAUAGUAUGUUUUAACAACUGGCAAGGCUAGUCCCCCUUAUAAUUUUUCCUAUUGUGCUUCUGGCUAUUCAUACAUGUUUGUUUUUCCAUGUGAACUUUAGUAUCAACUUGUCUAAAUUCAUUUUUUAAGGUACAUUGGUAUUUUAUUGAUAUUAUAUGAUAUUAACUGAUUUAGAGAGAACUAACAUCUUUAAAAUGUGGUGUCAUCCUAUCCAAGAAUAGGAGAUGUAUUUCCAUUUAUUCAAGUCUAUUUUGUGCCUUUUAGCAGUGUUUUAAAAUUAUCCUUGUGUAGGUUUUGUGCAUUUCUUGCUAAGCUUAUCCCUAAGUAUUUAAUUUAUUUGCUAGUA